AGGUGGUCUGCGCUGCAGACCUGGCGCAGGCUCGGGCCUCCUCCUGCUGCGGCUGUGCUCACCAAGCGAUGCCCCGCCGGCCCAGCGGCUACUUCUUGUCUUCUGGAGGCGCCGGCAGUGGCUCCGGUAGAGCCUUGGGCGAGGGCUCGGGCUCCCAGAGCAGGAAUUCGUGGAGCAGCGUGUUGACCGUCUCAGGGCAUUCCAGCAUCACCAUGUGGCUGCCCUCGUCGAUGAGCUUCAGGAAUGCCAGGAGCAGGAUCUGCAGAAGACGCAGGGCUCAAGGAGAGAAUGAGGCCACUUGGUAGUGGUCAAGCCCUGGGGACCAAGCCUUCCAUGGAGGGGUUCUUGGGCUGGAGCGGCUCUGGGCUCCGGAAUCGCCCGCAGCCGGUACUGCGGGACCCACUGCGGAUAUGGCUGUCUUGGCUGGAUCCCUGUUGGGCCCCACGAGUAGGUCGGCAGCGUUGCUGGGUGGCAGGUGGCUCCAGCCCCGGGCCUGGCUGGGGUUCCCAGACGCCUGGGGCCUCCCCACCCCGCAGCAGGCCCGGGGCAAGGCUCGCGGGAAUGAGUAUCAGCCGAGCAACAUCAAACGCAAGAACAAGCACGGCUGGGUCCGGCGCCUGAGCACGCCGGCCGGCGUGCAGGUCAUCCUUCGCCGAAUGCUCAAGGGCCGCAAGUCGCUGAGCCAUUGAGGAUCGCGACGCAGUCGGCGGGACCCUCAUGGAAGCAUCGCCCUCGCCUCGGACCUUGCCUGGCGCUAUUUUUGCAGGGAGCUGGGGAGCAGGAACGCCUCGGACCUGAGUGCUCUCCAUAUUGUGGGGUUGAAGUCUGGAUGGGAGCUUGCCAAGUCCCUUUUUAGGCUUUUUAAUUAGGAAGCAUUUCGAACCUGCGCAACAGACCAAAGAACAGUACAAAGAACAUCCGUGUACCCAGUACCCUGACUACCGACUACCUACAACCCGUCCCUGCCCCAUCCUGAGUUCUUUUGAAGCUGAUCUCAGGCAUCGGAUUAUUUCUUCUGUAAAUAUUUCAGAAUGUAUCUCUCCAAGAUGAGAGCUCAUUAAAAGACAAUUACAAAGCUUAUCACAUCCAAAAGAAUUAUCAAUAAUUUUGAAAUAUUAUUAAACGUGUAAUAAAUGUUCAAAGUUCCACUUGC